ACCAUAGAGUGAGGCGAGGAUGAAGCCGAGAGGAUACUGCAGAGGUCUCUGGUGCAUGUGUGUAUGUGUGCGUUUGUGUGUGUUUGUGUGUCUGUGUGUUCUGCCCCAGUGAGACUGCAGCCCUUGUAAAUACUUUGACACCUUUUGCAAGAAGGAAUCUGAACAAUUGCAACUGAAGGCACAUUGUUAUCAUCUCGUCUUUGGGUGAUGCUGUUCCUCACUGCAGAUGGAUAAUUUUCCUUUUAAUCAGAACAGCAUAAGAAUUAUUUCUGAGUGGAGGUGAGGCUUGUCCAAAUGUCUUUGCUAUCAUGGAUUUCCUGACUCCUACCUGUUUGAGGUUUGGGCAAUUAUGAAUAAGGCUGCUGUAUACAUCCGUGUGCAGGAUUUUGUGUGGACAUAAGUUUUCAACUCCUUUGGUUAAAUCCUAAGGAAUUUCAUAUGCAGAAUAAAUGGUAAUUAAAAUGUGCAGGAUGACAAGAUGGAGCAAACAGUGCUUGUACCACCAGGACCUGACAGCUUCAACUUCUUCACCAGAGAAUCUCUUGCGGCUAUUGAAAGACGCAUUGCAGAAGAAAAGGCAAAGAAUCCCAAACCAGACAAAAAAGAUGACGACGAAAAUGGCCCAAAGCCAAAUAGUGACUUGGAAGCUGGAAAGAACCUUCCAUUUAUUUAUGGAGACAUUCCUCCAGAGAUGGUGUCAGAGCCCCUGGAGGACCUGGACCCCUACUAUAUCAAUAAGAAAACUUUUAUAGUAUUGAAUAAAGGGAAGGCCAUCUUCCGGUUCAGUGCCACCUCUGCCCUGUACAUUUUAACUCCCUUCAAUCCUCUUAGGAAAAUAGCUAUUAAGAUUUUGGUACAUUCAUUAUUCAGCAUGCUAAUUAUGUGCACUAUUUUGACAAACUGUGUGUUUAUGACAAUGAGUAACCCUCCUGAUUGGACAAAGAAUGUAGAAUACACCUUCACAGGAAUAUAUACUUUUGAAUCACUUAUAAAAAUUAUUGCAAGGGGAUUCUGUUUAGAAGAUUUUACUUUCCUUCGGGAUCCAUGGAACUGGCUCGAUUUCACUGUCAUUACAUUUGCGUACGUCACAGAGUUUGUGGACCUGGGCAAUGUCUCGGCAUUGAGAACAUUCAGAGUUCUCCGAGCAUUGAAGACGAUUUCAGUCAUUCCAGGCCUGAAAACCAUUGUGGGAGCCCUGAUCCAGUCUGUGAAGAAGCUCUCAGAUGUAAUGAUCCUGACUGUGUUCUGUCUGAGCGUAUUUGCUCUAAUUGGGCUGCAGCUGUUCAUGGGCAACCUGAGGAAUAAAUGUAUACAAUGGCCUCCCACCAAUGCUUCCUUGGAGGAACAUAGUAUAGAAAAGAAUAUAACUGUGAAUUAUAAUGGUACACUUAUAAAUGAAACUGUCUUUGAGUUUGACUGGAAGUCAUAUAUUCAAGAUUCAAGAUAUCAUUAUUUCCUGGAGGGUUUUUUAGAUGCACUACUAUGUGGAAAUAGCUCUGAUGCAGGCCAAUGUCCAGAGGGAUAUAUGUGUGUGAAAGCUGGUAGAAAUCCCAAUUAUGGCUACACAAGCUUUGAUACCUUCAGUUGGGCUUUUUUGUCCUUGUUUCGACUAAUGACUCAGGACUUCUGGGAAAAUCUUUAUCAACUGACAUUACGUGCUGCUGGGAAAACGUACAUGAUAUUUUUUGUAUUGGUCAUUUUCUUGGGCUCAUUCUACCUAAUAAAUUUGAUCCUGGCUGUGGUGGCCAUGGCCUACGAGGAACAGAAUCAGGCCACCUUGGAAGAAGCAGAACAGAAAGAGGCCGAAUUUCAGCAGAUGAUUGAACAGCUUAAAAAGCAACAGGAGGCAGCUCAGCAGGCAGCAACGGCAACUGCCUCAGAACAUUCCAGAGAGCCCAGUGCAGCAGGCAGGCUCUCAGACAGCUCAUCUGAAGCCUCUAAGUUGAGUUCCAAGAGUGCUAAGGAAAGAAGAAAUCGGAGGAAGAAAAGAAAACAGAAAGAGCAGUCUGGUGGGGAAGAGAAAGAUGAGGAUGAAUUCCAAAAAUCUGAAUCUGAGGACAGCAUCAGGAGGAAAGGUUUUCGCUUCUCCAUUGAAGGGAACCGAUUGACAUAUGAAAAGAGGUACUCCUCCCCACACCAGUCUUUGUUGAGCAUCCGUGGCUCCCUAUUUUCACCAAGGCGAAAUAGCAGAACAAGCCUUUUCAGCUUUAGAGGGCGAGCAAAGGAUGUGGGAUCUGAGAACGACUUCGCAGAUGAUGAGCACAGCACCUUUGAGGAUAACGAGAGCCGUAGAGAUUCCUUGUUUGUGCCCCGACGACACGGAGAGAGACGCAACAGCAACCUGAGUCAGACCAGUAGGUCAUCCCGGAUGCUGGCAGUGUUUCCAGCGAAUGGGAAGAUGCACAGCACUGUGGAUUGCAAUGGUGUGGUUUCCUUGGUUGGUGGACCUUCAGUUCCUACAUCGCCUGUUGGACAGCUUCUGCCAGAGGGAACAACCACUGAAACUGAAAUGAGAAAGAGAAGGUCAAGUUCUUUCCACGUUUCCAUGGACUUUCUAGAAGAUCCUUCCCAAAGGCAACGAGCAAUGAGUAUAGCCAGCAUUCUAACAAAUACAGUAGAAGAACUUGAAGAAUCCAGGCAGAAAUGCCCACCCUGUUGGUAUAAAUUUUCCAACAUAUUCUUAAUCUGGGACUGUUCUCCAUAUUGGUUAAAAGUGAAACAUGUUGUCAACCUGGUUGUGAUGGACCCAUUUGUUGACCUGGCCAUCACCAUCUGUAUUGUCUUAAAUACUCUUUUCAUGGCCAUGGAGCACUAUCCAAUGACGGACCAUUUCAAUAAUGUGCUUACAGUAGGAAACUUGGUUUUCACUGGGAUCUUUACAGCAGAAAUGUUUCUGAAAAUUAUUGCCAUGGAUCCUUACUAUUAUUUCCAAGAAGGCUGGAAUAUCUUUGACGGUUUUAUUGUGACGCUUAGCCUGGUAGAACUUGGACUCGCCAAUGUGGAAGGAUUAUCUGUUCUCCGUUCAUUUCGAUUGCUGCGAGUUUUCAAGUUGGCAAAAUCUUGGCCAACGUUAAAUAUGCUAAUAAAGAUCAUCGGCAAUUCCGUGGGGGCUCUGGGAAAUUUAACCCUCGUCUUGGCCAUCAUCGUCUUCAUUUUUGCCGUGGUCGGCAUGCAGCUCUUUGGUAAAAGCUACAAAGAUUGUGUCUGCAAGAUCGCCAGUGAUUGUCAACUCCCACGCUGGCACAUGAAUGACUUCUUCCACUCCUUCCUGAUUGUGUUCCGCGUGCUGUGUGGGGAGUGGAUAGAGACCAUGUGGGACUGUAUGGAGGUUGCUGGUCAAGCCAUGUGCCUUACUGUCUUCAUGAUGGUCAUGGUGAUUGGAAACCUAGUGGUCCUGAAUCUCUUUCUGGCCUUGCUUCUGAGCUCAUUUAGUGCAGACAACCUUGCAGCCACUGAUGAUGAUAAUGAAAUGAAUAAUCUCCAAAUUGCUGUGGAUAGGAUGCACAAAGGAGUAGCUUAUGUGAAAAGAAAAAUAUAUGAAUUUAUUCAACAGUCCUUCAUUAGGAAACAAAAGAUUUUAGAUGAAAUUAAACCACUUGAUGAUCUAAACAACAAGAAAGACAGUUGUAUGUCCAAUCAUACAGCAGAAAUUGGGAAAGAUCUUGACUAUCUUAAAGAUGUAAAUGGAACUACAAGUGGUAUAGGAACUGGCAGCAGUGUUGAAAAAUACAUUAUUGAUGAAAGUGAUUACAUGUCAUUCAUAAACAACCCCAGUCUUACUGUGACUGUACCAAUUGCUGUAGGAGAAUCUGACUUUGAAAAUUUAAACACGGAAGACUUUAGUAGUGAAUCGGAUCUGGAAGAAAGCAAAGAGAAACUGAAUGAAAGCAGUAGCUCAUCAGAAGGUAGCACUGUGGACAUCGGCGCACCUGUAGAAGAACAGCCCGUAGUGGAACCUGAAGAAACUCUUGAACCAGAAGCUUGUUUCACUGAAGGCUGUGUACAAAGAUUCAAGUGUUGUCAAAUCAAUGUGGAAGAAGGCAGAGGAAAACAAUGGUGGAACCUGAGAAGGACGUGUUUCCGAAUAGUUGAACAUAACUGGUUUGAGACCUUCAUUGUUUUCAUGAUUCUCCUUAGUAGUGGUGCUCUGGCAUUUGAAGAUAUAUAUAUUGAUCAGCGAAAGACGAUUAAGACGAUGUUGGAAUAUGCUGACAAGGUUUUCACUUACAUUUUCAUUCUGGAAAUGCUUCUAAAAUGGGUGGCAUAUGGCUAUCAAACAUAUUUCACCAAUGCCUGGUGUUGGCUGGACUUCUUAAUUGUUGAUGUUUCAUUGGUCAGUUUAACAGCAAAUGCCUUGGGUUACUCAGAACUUGGAGCCAUCAAAUCUCUCAGGACACUAAGAGCUCUGAGACCUCUAAGAGCCUUAUCUCGAUUUGAAGGGAUGAGGGUGGUUGUGAAUGCCCUUUUAGGAGCAAUUCCAUCCAUCAUGAAUGUGCUUCUGGUUUGUCUUAUAUUCUGGCUAAUUUUCAGCAUCAUGGGCGUAAAUUUGUUUGCUGGCAAAUUCUACCACUGUAUUAACACCACAACUGGUGACAGGUUUGACAUCGAAGACGUGAAUAAUCAUACUGAUUGCCUAAAACUAAUAGAAAGAAAUGAGACUGCUCGAUGGAAAAAUGUGAAAGUAAACUUUGAUAAUGUAGGAUUUGGGUAUCUCUCUUUGCUUCAAGUUGCCACAUUCAAAGGAUGGAUGGAUAUAAUGUAUGCAGCAGUUGAUUCCAGAAAUGUGGAACUCCAGCCUAAGUAUGAAGAAAGUCUGUACAUGUAUCUUUACUUUGUUAUUUUCAUCAUCUUUGGGUCCUUCUUCACCUUGAACCUGUUUAUUGGUGUCAUCAUAGAUAAUUUCAACCAGCAGAAAAAGAAGUUUGGAGGUCAAGACAUCUUUAUGACAGAAGAACAGAAGAAAUACUAUAAUGCAAUGAAAAAAUUAGGAUCGAAAAAACCGCAAAAGCCUAUACCUCGACCAGGAAACAAAUUUCAAGGAAUGGUCUUUGACUUCGUAACCAGACAAGUUUUUGACAUAAGCAUCAUGAUUCUCAUCUGUCUUAACAUGGUCACAAUGAUGGUGGAAACAGAUGACCAGAGUGAAUAUGUGACUACCAUUUUGUCACGCAUCAAUCUGGUGUUCAUUGUGCUAUUUACUGGAGAGUGUGUACUGAAACUCAUCUCUCUACGCCAUUAUUAUUUUACCAUUGGAUGGAAUAUUUUUGAUUUUGUGGUUGUCAUUCUCUCCAUUGUAGGUAUGUUUCUUGCCGAGCUGAUAGAAAAGUAUUUCGUGUCCCCUACCCUGUUCCGAGUGAUCCGUCUUGCUAGGAUUGGCCGAAUCCUACGUCUGAUCAAAGGAGCAAAGGGGAUCCGCACGCUGCUCUUUGCUUUGAUGAUGUCCCUUCCUGCGUUGUUUAACAUCGGCCUCCUACUCUUCCUAGUCAUGUUCAUCUACGCCAUCUUUGGGAUGUCCAACUUUGCCUAUGUUAAGAGGGAAGUUGGGAUCGAUGACAUGUUCAACUUUGAGACCUUUGGCAACAGCAUGAUCUGCCUAUUCCAAAUUACAACCUCUGCUGGCUGGGAUGGAUUGCUAGCACCCAUUCUCAACAGUAAGCCACCCGACUGUGACCCUAAUAAAGUUAACCCUGGAAGCUCAGUUAAGGGAGACUGUGGGAACCCAUCUGUUGGAAUUUUCUUUUUUGUCAGUUACAUCAUCAUAUCCUUCCUGGUUGUGGUGAACAUGUACAUCGCGGUCAUCCUGGAGAACUUCAGUGUUGCUACUGAAGAAAGUGCAGAGCCUCUGAGUGAGGAUGACUUUGAGAUGUUCUAUGAGGUUUGGGAGAAGUUUGAUCCCGAUGCAACUCAGUUCAUGGAAUUUGAAAAAUUAUCUCAGUUUGCAGCUGCGCUUGAACCGCCUCUCAAUCUGCCACAACCAAACAAACUCCAGCUCAUUGCCAUGGAUUUGCCCAUGGUGAGUGGUGACCGGAUCCACUGUCUUGAUAUCUUAUUUGCUUUUACAAAGCGGGUUCUAGGAGAGAGUGGAGAGAUGGAUGCUCUACGAAUACAGAUGGAAGAGCGAUUCAUGGCUUCCAAUCCUUCCAAGGUCUCCUAUCAGCCAAUCACUACUACUUUAAAACGAAAACAAGAGGAAGUAUCUGCUGUCAUUAUUCAGCGUGCUUACAGACGCCACCUUUUAAAGCGAACUGUAAAACAAGCUUCCUUUACGUACAAUAAAAACAAAAUCAAAGGUGGGGCUAAUCUUCUUAUAAAAGAAGACAUGAUAAUUGACAGAAUAAAUGAAAACUCUAUUACAGAAAAAACUGAUCUGACCAUGUCCACUGCAGCUUGUCCACCUUCCUAUGACCGGGUGACAAAGCCAAUUGUGGAAAAACAUGAGCAAGAAGGCAAAGAUGAAAAAGCCAAAGGGAAAUAAAUGAAAAUAAAUAAAAAUAAUUGGGUGACAAAUUGUUUACAGCCUGUGAAGGUGAUGUAUUUUUAUCAACAGGACUCCUUUAGGAGGUCAAUGCCAAACUGACUGUUUUUACACAAAUCUCCUUAAGGUCAGUGCCUACAAUAAGACAGUGACCCCUUGUCAGCAAACUGUGACUCUGUGUAAAGGGGAGAUGACCUUGACAGGAGGUUACUGUUCUCACUACCAGCUGACACUGCUGAAGAUAAGAUGCACAAUGGCUAGUCAGACUGUAGGGACCAGUUUCAAGGGGUGCAAACCUGUGAUUUUGGGGUUGUUUAACAUGAAACACUUUAGUGUAGUAAUUGUAUCCACUGUUUGCAUUUCAACUGCCACAUUUGUCACAUUUUUAUGGAAUCUGUUAGUGGAUUCAUCUUUUUGUUAAUCCAUGUGUUUAUUAUAUGUGACUAUUUUUGUAAACGAAGUUUCUGUUGAGAAAUAGGCUAAGGACCUCUAUAACAGGUAUGCCACCUGGGGGGUAUGGCAACCACAUGGCCCUCCCAGCUACACAAAGUCGUGGUUUGCAUGAGGGCAUGCUGCACUUAGAGAUCAUGCAUGAGAAAAAGUCACAAGAAAAACAAAUUCUUAAAUUUCACCAUAUUUCUGGGAGGGGUAAUUGGGUGAUAAGUGGAGGUGCUUUGUUGAUCUUGUUUUGCGAAAUCCAGCCCCUAGACCAAGUAGAUUAUUUGUGGGUAGGCCAGUAAAUCUUAGCAGGUGCAAACUUCAUUCAAAUGUUUGGAGUCAUAAAUGUUAUGUUUCUUUUUGUUGUAUUAAAAAAAAAACCUGAAUAGUGAAUAUUGCCCCUCACCCUCCACCGCCAGAAGACUGAAUUGACCAAAAUUACUCUUUAUAAAUUUCUGCUUUUUCCUGCACUUUGUUUAGCCAUCUUCGGCUCUCAGCAAGGUUGACACUGUAUAUGUUAAUGAAAUGCUAUUUAUUAUGUAAAUAGUCAUUUUACCCUGUGGUGCACGUUUGAGCAAACAAAUAAUGACCUAAGCACAGUAUUUAUUGCAUCAAAUAUGUACCACAAGAAAUGUAGAGUGCAAGCUUUACACAGGUAAUAAAAUGUAUUCUGUACCAUUUAUAGAUAGUUUGGAUGCUAUCAAUGCAUGUUUAUAUUACCAUGCUGCUGUAUCUGGUUUCUCUCACUGCUCAGAAUCUCAUUUAUGAGAAACCAUAUGUCAGUGGUAAAGUCAAGGAAAUUGUUCAACAGAUCUCAUUUAUUUAAGUCAUUAAGCAAUAGUUUGCAGCACUUUAACAGCUUUUUGGUUAUUUUUACAUUUUAAGUGGAUAACAUAUGGUAUAUAGCCAGACUGUACAGACAUGUUUAAAAAAACACACUGCUUAACCUAUUAAAUAUGUGUUUAGAAUUUUAUAAGCAAAUAUAAAUACUGUAAAAAGUCACUUUAUUUUAUUUUUCAGCAUUAUGUACAUAAAUAUGAAGAGGAAAUUAUCUUCAGGUUGAUAUCACAAUCACUUUUCUUACUUUCUGUCCAUAGUACUUUUUCAUGAAAGAAAUUUGCUAAAUAAGACAUGAAAACAAGACUGGGUAGUUGUAGAUUUCUGCUUUUUAAAUUACAUUUGCUAAUUUUAGAUUAUUUCACAAUUUUAAGGAGCAAAAUAGGUUCACGAUUCAUAUCCAAAUUAUGCUUUGCAAUUGGAAAAGGGUUUAAAAUUUUAUUUAUAUUUCUGGUAGUACCUGCACUAACUGAAUUGAAGGUAGUGCUUAUGUUAUUUUUGUUCUUUUUUUCUGACUUCGGUUUAUGUUUUCAUUUCUUUGGAGUAAUGCUGCUCUAGAUUGUUCUAAAUAGAAUGUGGGCUUCAUAAUUUUUUUUUCCACAAAAACAGAGUAGUCAACUUAUAUAGUCAAUUACAUCAGGACAUUUUGUGUUUCUUACAGAAGCAAACCAUAGGCUCCUCUUUUCCUUAAAACUACUUAGAUAAACUGUAUUCGUGAACUGCAUGCUGGAAAAUGCUACUAUUAUGCUAAAUAAUGCUAACCAACAUUUAAAAUGUGCAAAACUAAUAAAGAUUACAUUUUUUAUUUUAUUGUUUGCCCAGUCACUUUUUGUUAACAGAAUAUUCUAAUGAUAUGGAGAUUUUUUACAUUACAAAUUGGGGGAGAAGGGGAGCGCGCGCGCACACACACACACACACACACACACACACACACACACACAGAGGCAUACCCACGUUGACAACAAAACCUAGGGUAGAUAUGUCACUGGAGGUAGGGGGUAAUGACCUCCCAGAAUUACAAGCAGCAGGUGUGUUCUCUGUUAGGAGGAAGAACUGGUGUCAGAGGAUAGCUAGUGAUUCUAGGAGGAAGAGAAGUAUGGAAGCCAGAGUGAUGGUGGAUGACCCCUUGAGCUAUGAAAAGAAACCCUUAAAUCAUCAUUUAAAAAUUUAGAAUUGCCAUGUGUGUAGGAUACUGUGUUUGCUCCUCCAGAGCCACUCUCUCUGCUUCUGCAUCAUUCUGUGUGUCCCAGAAGGGUGACUUCUACACAUUGCAAAAAUGGGCUCUCCUACCUUUGAGCUCCCAAUUGGUUUGGCCAAUGAGAAGCACCAGUGGGAAAGCACCAGAGAGAGAAGAUUGACAUAGGAAUAUUUCUUCUCCAAUUCCUUCUUUGCUGGGUUGGCACUGGACUCAUUCCUCCCCGAAAAGUCAUACUCCAAUCAGACUGCCCCUCAUACAACUGAAGCUACUUUCUCUGGGGUCAGGUAAUCACUCCUCCCCUUGCUCCUUCAGGUCUGCUGCUGCAUUGAGAGUGCUUUUGUAUUCCUUGUAGCUUUCUCCUAACAUUGCUGACACUUUUGUAAAUGUCCCCUUCAUGAAAUUCUUCUAUAUGCCUCAUUUCAGCAUGCCAUCUGUCUCCUGCCUGGCUGACACAAGGUGAUUCAACAGCUCAUGAAAGUCAGCAGGAAGCAAAGAUGUGCCUUGCUUCAGCUUGGGGUCUUAAUCUUGCUAACUUUUGCAGAUAAAGAAAAACAGUAACUGGGGGAACCACAGUGAAGUCCAGUGCAGAAUUCACAGAUAUCAUGGAAAGGUUACUCGGGUGGUCCAGAUAGUAAAAUUAACAGUCUAAAUUAAUCUAUCUAAAUUUCUGAGGAACGAGAAGCCUUCCCUUGUCAUCAGGUGAAGCCAGAAGAGGGAAUAUAGCCUCAACCAGAAAAGGGACAGUAAUUAAAAGGCUUUUCCCAUCCUUGUACAAUGGACUGACUUUGCCUCUUCAUAACAUCACAAUCCUAAAGCAACACAACAAUUAAUUCUGAUAUAUUAGUAGCUGAAAAAAAUUCCCAUUUCCAACUAAGGUAGGUCAGAAUUAUAGGAUAAACCCUGCAGACUUUUUAUACUACCCAUCCACGCCAUUACUCACUGUUACCUUUCCAAAUACAAAGAGAAGAACUGGUAAAACAUAAUCAUAUAAAUCUCCAUAUUCAUUUUGAAAUAUUUGGCAUGAUAUUUUCUGUGCUAAAAAGUAAUUAUUCUUCAAAGAAUGAUGAGGUCAUGUCAGUAAGACACAGGAACCAACUAGAAGGGGCUUCCCACUGGCCAAAUCUGGGGCAAGUUGAGCAUCAAAAUAAAUGAUAGUAAAAGAUUAUAAUUCAUUGAAUAAGAAUCAGCAAAUACAUACUGAUGUAAGUAAAUAAGGAAAAGUACAAAUCUGUUUCUUGCAGUUGAAUGUUAAUUAACAAUUGUAGAAGAAAUAACGGAGUUAGAAAAAUCACUAUUUGGCAAUCACCCUAAUGACAAUUGAUUCAUACAAGAAUCAUCAAUGAGUAUUAAAACUCAUGGGUGAAAGUUUGAUGAGGAAUAGGGUAUUUAUAGCAUCUUAAAGUAUCUCUUCUCUAUUAAGUAGAAAAUUUAAACAGAAGAAAGUAUACUUUGGAGAAAUACAGCAGACAAUACCUUCAAAGAUAUCAUCAAUUAUGAGACCAACUGAUACUAUGUGCCUCCUGAUAAGAUAUACUGAAAGGGCCACAUUACUUCUUGGUACACAGUCAAAAUUUUAAAACCAGAAUCUAACUACAAGGAAAAUCAAAUUGAGGACACUCUAUAAAAUAAGUGGACUGAACUCCUUAAAAAUGUCAAUGUCAUGAAAGACAAAGAAAGGCUAAAGAAUUCCAUGAGGUCAAAGAACUAUGACAACUAAACACAAUUCUGGAUGGAAUAUCAAAUUAAAAAAUAACAGAUAAAUAAUAUUAUUGGGAAAGUUGAAUAAAUUUGAAUAUGGACUGUUUAUUAGUUAUUAGUAUUAUAAUAGUGUUAAUUUUCCUAAUUUUGUUAAGACUAGUGUGCCUGUUCCAUGAAAAUAGAAAAUGUUCUUAUUCUCUGAAAAUGCAUGCUAAAGUAUUUAGGGGUGAAUGCAACAAUGUCUGCAGCUCAUUCUUGAAUCAGUUCAAAGAAAAAUGAGUUACAUUUAUAUAUAUAUGUAUGUAUGUAAACAGACAUAGAUAAAAGUAUAGAUGUGUGUGUGUCUUUAGAAAGGGGAGGAUUUUUUUUUUUUUUUUGCUGUGUGUUACUGAAGUGCCUAUGUCUGCGUGUUCACACUAUCAUAUUUUGUAUGCCCUGGACUUUAUAAUUUCUACCUUCAAAAUUAGAUCUACUGUUGGUAAUUAAUUCAAUAUAUACUGGUUUUUUAACUACUAUUCUCAUUUCCUAGCAGUAAUCUUCCUGAAAAGUCACAGAAAUGAUUACAUUCCUUGUUCUUCAUAAUAAUCACUGUUUAAUUAAAAUAAGAAUAUUUUAGAAAAGAUCUGCGGCAUAGUGGUUAAGACCCCAGUAUUUGAUGCUAAACAGAUCUGAUUUGGAUAACAGAAGGUGGCACUUUGCUGUUUAAGCUGGGGACCAGACACUGUGGGUAUAAAUAGUAAUUCCAAACACAGCUCCACAGAGCAGCACCCUUAUGACAAGGUUUUCAUAUGUCUAUAGUUAAGCCAGAAAAUUAAGAAUAAUGCCAUAAAUAUUUAUAAAGCUGAACAUAUCCAAGUUAAAGACCUUUAUCCUGAAAUUGUAUCUUUUAGAUUAUUUUCUAAAGACUAAUACCAUUUAAUGUUUAAAUGUUCUUUGGAAAUGAUGGUGAGAAUACGUGAUAAUGGGUCAUUGGUUUUAAUAUUUUAUUUAGCCAAGUGGAAAAUUGGCAACCUGGUGUCGGUCCUCCCAUUUGUAUUUUACUGGUGCAUGAAAUCCAAAAGUCUAGUAACCAUUGGGACAGACAACUCUACUGCAUAAGUUUGUAUGUUUGUAUAUCUGUAUCACAAAGCCCAGACACUCGAACUAUAUAAACUUGUCGCACUAAAGACAGCAAAUAUGUCUGGUAAUUGCAUAUUCUUCAUGUGUGCACUGGAAUUUCUUAUUAUAUAAGAAAAUAAAUGUGUUUCUAAACCACCAUGAAUUGGGUACUGCUGAUAGUACUAUUCUUCCUGGCACAUGGAAAUAUCCCACUGAGGUUGUCAAUCAAUAUUGAUUUAAUCAGUGUGGCAGCAAAGGCACUAGAGGAGGAAAAUACUCUAGACAAUCAAGUAUAGAUGGGAAAAUUGCAUCACCAAGAAAUUCUUAAAAUCACAAGUGGAUAAUUUGCAAUAUCAAUUGAUUUUACUCAACUGCUUGAGUCCUUUAUCAUUCCGUUAGAACACUCCUCAUAUUUGCAGAUAACUCAGCCCCUCACCUCAGCAACAAGCAAGAGGACAUCAUUAUAAACUUCCUCAAUUUCUUUCCUAUCCAGUGAAAAAUAUCUAAGUCCCUUUUCCCUUCCCUUUUCCUUCCCUUCCCUUCCUUUUUCUUUCCUUCCAUUCUCUUCCUUUUUCCUUCCUUUUUCUUUCCUUCCAUUCUCUUCCUUUUUCCUUCCUUUUUCUUACUUUACCUCCCCCUCCUACCUUUCCCUUUCUCCCUUCCUCCCUCUCUCCCUUCCUUCCUCUCUCCCUCUCCUUCCUUCCUUCCUUCAAUCCAUACUUUUAUAUCUUUUCAGAGAUCAAUUUUUCCCAUUCAUUUCUACAUUCUCAGAUACCUUGCUCCAUGACUUGUUCUACUUCUCUUCUAUCUUUAUUCUUUCCCUCUUGACUGAUCCUUUUUGUCUGCCUUUGCAUUUUCAAAAUCAGUUUUUCUAAUCUUAAAAAAUAACUUUGCUCAACCCUGAUGCAUCUUUAUUCACUGUGUCAUUAUCUCAUUAUUUUUAAAGGUUAGUUUCUAAAGCCAGGGCUCUAUACUCACUACCUUCACUCUUGGUUAAAAUUAAAAGAAAUAUAGGUCCCAGUGAUAUUUAUGGGAAAAUUUGACUGUGAAUAAUCUUGUUGAUAUAAACACUUUGGGUUUUCAAAAUGUUAUGCUAGCUGUUAACUUUCCCAGUAACAUUAUGAGGGAAGGGCUGGAAAAUACAAAAGGUAGACAUAGGAACCGAGAACACCACCCCUAUGGAGCCAAGCUAUACAUACUCUGUCUCUGGUUAUCAUAAAUACAUCUCCUAUAUUCAAUGCUUGCUUAGAAAGGCAUGAUGUCCACGGAGCAAUUCAAUUGUUCACUGUGAUGGGUUUUUUUGUUUUCUCCUCAUGGAAUGCAACUUUUAUUUAU